CUGCUGGGCAGGCGGGCAGCCCCGGAGAUUCCGCAGUCCCCCCAGGAGGUUCAAGAGCCACUGAUCAGGAUAAGCGCUGCCGGAGGAACAAACCCAGAGAGAAAUGUUCCCGGGGACUCCCUCCACUGAGCUGGCGCACUCCUAACAGCAGCCAUCAGUUUGGGGACCCCGGACAGCCCGGGGAUCCCGAAGGCCGCGAGGACCAAGGACCAGGCGCUGGGGUGGGUGUGGAGGACAUGGAGCCCGUGGUUUAGGCCUGAGGUGCCCAUGUUGGGUGGCAGCAAGAGGCAGGGUGGGCGGGUCUGUGGCCAUGCCCAUGGGUGCUGCGGAACGGGGUGCGGGCCCUCAGAGUUCCGCGGCGCCAUGGGCUGGCUCUGAGAAGGCGUGCACCGACCUCCUGAGAGGGGCCACACUUGUCUAGGGCGAUGGCUCUUGUUAGGGAGUCAUUGGAAGCCACCCUAAAGGGCGAAAAGAGGCCCUAGCAAGUCCUGGUACCCAAGAGCUGCUGCUAGCGAUGUGACUUGCCCCACUGGUGGAGACGGUGCAGACCCCAAGCCGGGGCCAUUCGGUGGAGGCCUCGCUCUGGGUCCAGCUCCACGCGGCACCAUGAACAAUAACUUCUGCCGGGCUCUGGUGGACCGGAGGCCUCUGGGGCCCCCCAGCUGCAUGCAGCUGGGCGUCAUGCCCCCUCCCCGGCAGGCGCCCCUGCCCCCCGCCGAGCCCCUGGGCAACGUGCCCUUCCUGCUGUACCCGGGCCCAGCAGAGCCGCCCUACUACGACGCCUAUGCGGGGGUGUUCCCCUACGUGCCCUUCCCCGGCGCCUUCGGGGUCUACGAAUACCCCUUCGAGCCAGCCUUCAUCCAGAAGCGCAACGAGCGCGAGAGGCAGCGAGUCAAGUGCGUCAACGAGGGCUACGCUCGCCUCCGCGGCCACCUCCCCGGCGCCCUGGCUGAGAAGCGACUCAGCAAGGUGGAGACGCUGCGCGCCGCCAUCCGCUACAUAAAGUACCUGCAAGAGCUGCUGAGCUCGGCCCCCGACGGCUCGACGCCCCCCGCUUCCCGCGGCCUCCCGGGCACCGGGCCCUGCCCCGCGCCGCCCGCCACCCCCCGUCCCGACCGCCCUGGCGACGGCGAGGCCCGGGCGCCCUCCUCCCUGGUGCCGGAGUCAUCCGAGUCCUCCUGCUUCUCCCCGUCGCCUUUCUUGGAGUCGGAGGAAUCCUGGCAUUGAUCGGGCCUGUGGCCGCCCCCGGCUUGGAGGAUGAUCCGCCGGCCCCGUCCCACUUUCGGGAGCAGCGGGAGGCUGUUGGGUCACCCGCGAUGCGCCGCAGGACGGUGACUGUAGGAGGUCCGCGGCGCUCCCGUGUCUGCGACACCCUCCCUCCUCCACCAGCUUGGGGCGGAAGUGCAGGGCAGCGGGUACGAUGGGCACGAUAGAGACCUAGGAGCUCCGUGGGUGAAGCGAGGGGCAGGGCCUGGGACUGCUCCGGGCGUCCUGCGUCCCCUCCGGGGUGCAGAGGGGCUCCCCAGGACGGUCAUCCCUGGGUCUGGCUCCCGCUCGGCCUCAGGUGGCUCUGCUCCGUCCUUCCUUGCCGCAGGCGCAGUCCAGUCUCUGCGAGUCCCCGGGAUGCGAGCCCGACUUUGAGCCCUCGGUUACCAUGCCACUGCUCUCCACCAGAUGGCCUCAGAUACUAGCGACUUCUUUGGGAGCACGCUUACUCCUCGAGAAAGGAACCCAGAGGAAGGGAUGGGAGGCCAGAUUGCUGCUGGCGCUCAGCCCAGACCGAACCUACAGACUCAGCAGAGGCGACCUGUGUGCCCCGGUGGCGUUCUCUGGCUUCCUGGGUUGGGAGGGGGGGUUACUCCCUCCCCGCAUCCCCCCCAUGAGGUCGUCUAGUUUUGUCCCAGGUUGGGUGGGGACUGUGGUUUUUUUCCCUCAGACUGUAAGCCUUGGGGGAGGGGGGCGUGCAUAUAGGUACAUAGGCACUGCGUCGGCACCAAAGAGCUAAAUAAAAGGAUUGUUGAAUUUUCUCAUUCCUA